GCUGGGCCUGUGAUCGCUGAGGGGCGAGCAGUUGCGACCCUGGGCUCCUGGGGACCUGAGCGUUAUGUCUUUCCGCGACCUCCGCAGUAAGGCAGCCCCGCGCCCCUGUGACCUGCGGGUCUUCCAGAGAUUCAGGGCUCCCGCCCGCCGGGUCCCCUGUGUAGGCGAUCCCUGAGGCUUGCGCUGCCGGAGGCUCCUUUCGGGCCUCUGCGCCUCAGGGACCGCCUGACCCGCGGCUGCAACCCGGCCGAGCGUCCCAGGCCCUUCUUCGGCCAUUUCUAGCGAGGAUGGAAAGUUCUCUAUCUGCCACUGGCCGCGUGUGGCUCAGAACGCUUGAAAUGUGGCUAGUGCAGAUGAAUAACUGAAUUUUUAAGUGUAAUUUAUUUCUGUUUGUGUAGCUGCAUGCCGCUCUUCGCUACCGUAUUGGAAAAUGCAUGGAGAGUUUAGAGACUAUUUUUUGAGUUGGGUUAGCUUAGCGCUUAGAAAACCGAACAGCAGGCCGGGCGCGGUGGCUCACGCCCGUAAGCCCAACACUUUGGGAGGCCGAGGCGGGCGAAUCACCUGAGGUCGGGAGUUCGAGACCAGCCUGACCAACAUGGAGAAACCCCGUCUCUACUAAAAUUACAAAAUUAGCCGGGGGUGGUGGCGGGCGCCUGUAAUCCCAGCUACUCGGGAGUCUGAAGCAGGAGAAUCGCUUUGGAGGUUGCGGUGAGCCGAGAUCGGGCCAUUGCACUCCAGCCUAGGCAACAAGAGCGAAACAACAUCUCAAAAAACAAAAAACAAACCAAAAAAAAAACAACCAGCAACGAAACCGAGGAGAGGAGGCUGGGUGAUAAUCAUUGCGGCUAACAUUUUUUGAGUUUUAACGAUCUGCCAGGGCCCGCUCUGUGUUAUGCGCAUUUCAUUUUAAUCAUCUGAACAACUCUGUGCCCCCUGUAUUUGGUAGUGAGGAAACGGGCACAGAGAGGUCAGGUAACUUGGGCAGGUGAUACAGGCGGUAGGAGGUGGCACUGGGGCUUGAAUUCAGGUUGCCUGAACUCCAGACAUCCUGAACUCCAUCUGCAUCCUUUCUGCAGGGCUGAUUUCACAGAGAUGAUGAGAGCCCUGGGAUACCCUCGACAUAUUUCUAUGGAAAAUUUCCGUACACCCAAUUUUGGACUUGUAUCUGAAGUGCUUCUCUGGCUUGUGAAAAGAUAUGAGCCCCAGACUGACAUCCCGCCUGACGUGGAUACUGAACAGGACCGAGUUUUCUUCAUUAAGGCAAUUGCCCAGUUCAUGGCCACCAAGGCACAUAUAAAACUCAACACUAAGAAGCUUUAUCAAGCAGAUGGGUAUGCGGUAAAAGAGCUGCUGAAGAUCACAUCUGUCCUUUAUAAUGCUAUGAAGACCAAGGGGAUGGAGGGCUCUGAAAUAGUAGAGGAAGAUGUCAACAAGUUCAAGUUUGAUCUUGGCUCAAAGAUUGCAGAUUUGAAGGCAGCCAGGCAGCUUGCGUCUGAAAUCACCUCCAAAGGAGCAUCUCUGUAUGACUUGCUCGGCAUGGAAGUAGAGUUGAGGGAAAUGAGAACAGAAGCCAUUGCCAGACCUCUGGAAAUAAACGAGACUGAAAAAGUGAUGAGAAUUGCAAUAAAAGAGAUUUUGACACAGGUUCAGAAGACUAAAGACCUGCUCAAUAAUGUGGCCUCUGAUGAAGCUAAUUUAGAAGCCAAAAUCGAAAAGAGAAAAUUAGAACUGGAAAGAAAUCGGAAGCGACUAGAGACUCUGCAGAGUGUCAGGCCAUGUUUUAUGGAUGAGUAUGAGAAGACUGAGGAAGAAUUACAAAAGCAGUAUGACACUUAUCUGGAGAAAUUUCAAAAUCUGACUUAUCUGGAACAACAGCUUGAAGACCAUCAUAGGAUGGAGCAAGAAAGGUUUGAGGAAGCUAAAAACACUCUCUGCCUGAUACAGAACAAGCUCAAGGAGGAAGAGAAGCGCCUGCUCAAGAGUGGAAGUAACGAUGACUCGGACAUAGACAUCCAGGAGGACGAUGAAUCCGACAGUGAGUUGGAAGAAAGGCGGCUGCCCAAGCCACAGACAGCCAUGGAGAUGCUCAUGCAAGGAAGACCUGGCAAACGCAUUGUGGGCACGAUGCAAGGUGGAGACUCCGAUGACAAUAUGGAAGCAGCACCAGCUCUCUUAGGUAAAUGCAAGACUUCCAGCUCCAAGAAGCAGGAGGACUCGGAGGAGAGUGAAAUUGACAUGGAAGAUGAUGAUGACGAGGAUGACGAUUUGGAAGACGAGAGCAUUUCUCUCUCACCAACCAAGCCCAAUCGAAGGGUCCGGAAAUCUGAACCCCUGGAUGAGAGUGACAAUGACUUCUGACCCUUUUGCCAAGGGACCCUGGCAGAUUAAAACCCUCAGACUUGUAGGUAAAUGGGAACUUAGAAGGUUAGGAAGGUAACCCCUGUUUUGUUUACUAAGCUGGCUGGACUCAUGAUCACUGAAGCAAUACUUAUUUCUGCUUUAGCCUCCUAUGUUUGCAUUCCAUGAAGCUUAAAUAAGAAUUGAAGCAAAUCCCUAAGAUUUAUUUUUUUCCACCUUAUUUAUCUUCUAAAACUUGAGGAAUGCAUGUGUUCUUAGUGAUUCACAUCCACGGGACAAAAACUCAAGAAGAAAUAAGAGCUGACGCCACACAAGUCUUGGCUGCUUUUGUUACUAUACAUUUUCUCUGAGACUCCAGCAGAGUUGGGGCUGGAACUUGGCACUGGGGACUCAUGUUUGGAAUCGUAGGGGAACAUCUGGCUGUUAAUCACUUGCACAGUUGAGAACAUUUCCUAUACAUCGGCUUUUAAUUCUAGCUCUUAUUUCAUUUUGUAAUCUUAUUUUCUUUCGUCUGCAUGUUCACAAUACCAAGCAUUAAAUGUAUUUUAAUAACUAAACUUUUCUGAAAGAAGGUUAGCUAAAGUUAAAUGAAAACUUGGUUUCUUUGAAAAUCAGGCAAUAGAGACAGGCUCCAGAUGAGGAAUCCUCCAUUUUCUGUCCGAAGCUGACAUUCCUCUGGCAGUCCAGUUCACCUUGGAUUACAGCCACCUUCAUGUUUCCACGGUUGGUACUAAAUCUGGAAACUCUGGUGACCUGGGCUGCCCUCUCAGAAACUCCAGACUCCCAUGGCAAUGACAGCCGGGACACUUUUCUUCCCUCCAGCCAGGGUUUCUCUAAAGGAGCUUUGUUUUGUCUAAAGUGUGGCAAGACAUAGUGCACAACACAGGGACAAAGGCAGGUUUCCUGCAGCUCGCUACCUAAGUGUUUCUGUAGGGGAAGGAGCCAAUUAAGAAAAAGUGUUGGUACAGAUUCAUGUUUCUGAUUUAAAAAAACAACAACACAGGAUUGAAUUAAGUAGAGUAAUAGCACUAGAAGAAUUUUUCUGUUGUGAAAUUAGAAGUGGAGUUGGUUUUUUUCUUUUUUCUUCUUCUUUUUUUUUAAUAUGAAAAGUACUUAGCUGGGAGUGGUGGCAAGCGCCCUUGGGUCCAGCUACUCAGGAGGCCAAGGUGGGAGGAUCACUUGAGCCCAGGAGUUUUAGACUAGCCUGGACAACUAAGUGAGACUCCAUCUCUACAAAAAAUUAAAAAAUUAGCCAGGUGUGGAGGGGCAUGCCUGUGGUCUCAGCUAUUCAGGAGGCUGAGGCAGGAGAAUCACUUGAGACCAGGAAGUUGAGGCUGCAAUGAGCCGUGAUCAUGCCACUGCACUCCAGCCUGGGUGACAGAGUGAGACCCUGUCUUUAAAAAAAAGAAAAAGAAAAGCACGCUGCUUGUAAAAAGCGUACAGUAGGUCAGGCGUGGUGGCUCAUGCCUGUAAUCCUAGCACUUUGAGAGGCUGAGGUGGGUAGAUCACCUGAGGUCAGGGGUUUGAGACCAGCCUGGCCAACAUGGCGAAACCCCACCUCUACUAAAAAUACAAAAAUUAGCCGGGCGUGGUAGCGCAUGCCUGUAACCCCAGCUACUGGGGAGGCUGAGGCAGGAGAAUCGCUUGAACCUAGGAGGCGGAGGUUGCAGUGAGCCGAGAUGGCGCCACUGCACUCCAGCCUGGGCAGCAGAGUGAGACUCCAUCUCAAAAAAAAAAAAAAAAAAAAAAGCAUACAGUAAAUAAAAAAGCACAAAACAGUUUUCACUUAUUUUACAAUUAAAAAGUCAGAAGACUUCUGAAGUUACUUAUCUUUUAAUACAUGUAUUUAACACCAUACUUCAUAUUAUUAAAUAGGUUUUACUUAAAAAUAUAAUUAUUGUAUUUGUACCUGUCAGAUAUAAAUACUUAUUCAGGAGUUCACAGGUACGAAAAGAUACACAUAAAUUUUAGGAACUUUUGAGUUAUUUCUGUCAUUUUUGCUUUUUUCUCUUUCUUUUCCUAAAUUUUAUGUAUAAGAUUACCCCUAAAAAAAAAAAAACAGCCAGUAUUCAGUGAAUUCACCAGUAAUUUGAAAUGCACCAUAUUGUAAAUGAUCCACUGACAGGGAAGCCAGCGUGUUGGAGCCAUGCCAGCCACCUCAGACACCGUGGCUCUAAGAUGCGGAAGAGUCACUGCAUCUUCUUGAAUGUUACAGAUUUGGUUUGCCUGAAUGUGACUUGACUUCUGUUUUGAAAAAACAUACGAAUAGAGUUCUAUUUUCCUUAUGUGAUGCUUUCUUCUAACACACUUUAACACAGAAGCCUAACCUAGCUACAAAGAGCCUAUCCACAGACAUAGGCAACAGCUCCAAAGGGUAUUUCAUUGUGUCACCUGCUUCUAGAUCAUCUGUUAGUUAACUGACUUUGUGCAAGGUCUCACCAUGUAUAGCACUGCCUUGCUUGAGCACGGAAGUUUCUGUCAACAGCAAGCUUUAUGUGCUCUAUCAUUUUUAUUAAAGUAUUUCAGUCAAUAGUGACCCAUUGUAGAAUGGAUGCAGGAUUCACAUGUGCAAGUGCUUUGUGACCUGGCACCAUUUGGUUUUGGCCAAGCAGCAGAGCAGACCUCAGGACCUAACGAGGAUGGUUGUGAUUAGGUCAAAUAGAAAACUAGCAGGCCAUUGCUGACAAUUUUUACUAUAUAAUUAGAGGACUUCCUAAAAUGCUUUAAAAAAAAAUGUGUAUGGAUGGAAAAUACAAAGGAAUUUUUCAAAUACUCAA